ACUCCACAUACCACCAGCACCGCUAAUACCCCUGUAGAAGGAGCUCUCCAGGAUGAAGCUCCAGACUGGGUUGUAGGGGGCUCAGACAAAAGAGAAACUGCCCGUCUUCAAGAACCUUCAAUCUAAUGGGGAGACAGGUGAACCCUCGCCCCCGUGGGAACUGCCAGUUGGAUAGGGAAGAAGGGACACAGCAGAGAGUCACAGCACACAGGAAGACUAUGUCACACUGCCAGGUGCUGUGGGAGGACAAAGACAGUCAGUGCUGGGGGCAUCUGGACUGGGUGUGGGCCCAUGUGAGCAGGAGCAGUCAGAGAGGCCUCCCUGGGGGAGGAGGCAUUGGAGCUGAUCUGGGACGGAAGGGACGGAUUUGGAGAGGACAGCAGAGGCCCUUAACUGCAACCUGGGCAGAGCAGAGGGCCUGGCCGCCUCUCAGAAUGGCCUCCACCCUGGCCCAGGGCAAGGACCCGCCCAUGGAGAAGGCCCUGAGCAUGUUUUCCGAUGACUUUGGCAGCUUCAUGCGGCCCCACUCGGAGCCCCUGGCCUUCCCAGCCCGCCCCGGUGGGGCAGGCAACAUCAAGACCCUAGGAGACGCCUAUGAGUUUGCGGUGGACGUGAGAGACUUCUCACCUGAAGACAUCAUUGUCACCACCUCCAACAACCACAUCGAGGUGCGGGCUGAGAAGCUGGCGGCUGACGGCACUGUCAUGAACACCUUCGCUCACAAGUGCCAGCUGCCGGAGGACGUGGACCCGACGUCGGUGACCUCGGCUCUGCGGGAGGACGGCAGCCUCACUAUCCGGGCACGGCGUCACCCGCAUACAGAACACGUCCAGCAGACCUUCCGGACGGAGAUCAAAAUCUGAGUGCCUCUCCCUUCCCUUUCCCUGUCCCCCCGCCCCACGCCUGCCAGCAAAGCCUCGCUAACCCCAUUACAACAGCUCCAGGACAUCUCAGCCCAGGUUCUAGCCCCCACGCACCCCAGACCCCAGGUGGACCAUCCUCCCAAACUAGGGCCCUCCACUCUAUCCAGGGCAGGCCAGGGACUCCCUGGCCUGACACAUGAUGCCCAGAUUUCAGAUUUGGCCUCCGUCACUUAAUCCAGAGUACAGGGGCUGGGGUCAGGGAAGGAAGAUCUAAAGAACCCACUGUGGGUCAGGGGAAUGGGACCAGCAGGACAUAUGGGCAAGCUCUGCAGGACAGACAGACAGACAAACCCUCUGAUCUAUGAAGUCUCUGCAGGGCAAGGGGACCAGGGACCUGGAACCCUCUUGGCCAAGGGGAGUGGGAGGGACAGAGGGAAGGUCACAGGCAAGGGUGCCUAUCUAAGUGGAACUAAUUGCCCGAGGGCUCAGCAAGGCCAAGAGGAGACAGCCGUGACGGUAAACUUCCCCUCUACCAGCCUCCAAGCCCCACGCCAGCGAGCAGGCUGCCUGCCCACCCCGUGCCCCCAGCCAGCUGGCUGUGCCAGGGCAGAGCCAUGCCACAUCUGUAUAUAGAUGGGGUUUUUCCAAUACAGCUGGUUCGUGAUAAACUGCAUGAAACUCCUGCCGUCCUGCGCCUGCUGGGGCCUCCAGGCAAGGCCAAGUGGGGUUGGGGGUGGGGCUGGUCCUUCUCCCUCCCACAGGCCUGUGUUCUUGGGGCUGCUCCCAUGCAGACAGGAUCACCUAACAGAGAUGGAAGCCAGGGCAUGGAUGGGGCUUUGGGUCCUCGAGGUUGGACCCCAGCUUCUUGCCACCUUCCCCUCCGGGCAGUCAGCUCUCCAUCCAUCCCCCUCUUUAAUCUAUGAAUCUAUAGGCUCGGUGUGUGUAACACACACACCCCUAUCGUUGUCCUUCAAAUACUCAGCAUUACCAUUGGUUGAGGCCAAAUUCAGAGCUUUCUCAAAUCAGAUUUACAAUCUCCAUUUUCAUUAACGGGGAAACAUCCCCGAGCCACUGAGUGCUGUGCUUUGUCACUGAAGGUUAGAUCUGAACCCAGGGUGUCAACUGCUGCUCUCAACUCCCCACCUCUGGGCACUGAGGAGUAUUUCCCCUCAUUCUACCUCUCUAAGGCUAUGCAACCCUCCCCACGUCUUCCAGCUGGGGGAUGGGGGGGAGUCAUAGGAAAAGCCCCCAUCUCCCAUCUGGGAUAGGGACCUUCCAUCAGCCUUAACCCUGGGAAAUGCCUGCUGCCCCCAAUGACUCUUGGUUUCGUCUCCCACAUACAGAAGCAGGGUGGAGGGGAAGGGUGGGUCUCAGUUAGCAGGGGUCCCCAGGGCAAGUCAGCCUCCUCCCUCCAUGCCUCUCUGGUCAGUGUGCCUUAGGGUGGCCUCUCACUCCCACCACUCUGGGCCCCUUGGGGGAGGACUGGGGAGGGGGCCGUGGGAGAGCCCUGACGCUGGAACCUGUAUACACAAUAAAGGACAGUCUCACAGA